GUUGUUGGCUGACUUCCGGUGGUGCCAAAGCCGUUUCCGUGGAAUCAGGCCGGCUGAAUGGAACAAAAGUGGGACUUUUAAAAUGUUGCCCUGUAAGAAGAGAAGAACUACAGUGACAGAGUCCCUACAGCAUAAAGGCAAUCAAGAGGAAAACAACGUAGACCUAGAAUCAGCCGUUAAACCAGAAUCUGACCAGGUUAAGGACUUGAGUUCGGUGUCACUAUCCUGGGAUCCAAGUCAUGGCAGAGUAGCUGGCUUCGAAGUACAGUCUUUGCAGGAUGCAGGAAAUCAGCUUGGUAUGGAGGAUACAUCUCUGAGCUCUGGAAUGCUCACCCAGAACACAAAUGUACCAAUUCUAGAAGGUGUUGAUGUGGCCAUCUCUCAGGGAAUCACCCUACCUUCCUUGGAGUCUUUUCACCCCCUUAAUAUACACAUUGGUAAAGGAAAACUCCACGCUACUGGCUCAAAGAGAGGGAAAAAAAUGACACUCAGGCCUGGGCCAGUUACCCAAGAAGACAGAUGUGAUCAUCUUACCCUAAAGGAGCCUUUUUCAGGAGAGCCUAGUGAAGAAGUCAAGGAAGAAGGAGGGAAACCUCAAAUGAAUUCUGAAGGGGAGAUACCUUCCCUGCCAUCAGGCAGCCAAUCUGCAAAACCAGUAAGCCAGCCCAGGAAAUCAACCCAGCCAGAUGUUUGUGCCUCUCCUCAAGAAAAGCCACUCAGGACUCUGUUUCACCAACCUGAGGAAGAGAUAGAAGAUGGUGGACUCUUCAUUCCAAUGGAAGAACAAGACAAUGAAGAAAGUGAGAAAAGGAGAAAAAAGAAAAAGGGUACCAAGAGGAAACGAGAUGGAAGGGGUCAAGAAGGGACCUUGGCAUAUGACCUGAAACUGGAUGACAUGCUUGACCGUACCUUGGAGGAUGGUGCCAAGCAGCACAAUCUAACAGCAGUCAAUGUCCGAAACAUCCUUCAUGAAGUAAUCACAAAUGAACACGUGGUAGCUAUGAUGAAAGCAGCCAUCAGUGAGACGGAAGAUAUGCCAAUGUUUGAGCCUAAAAUGACACGCUCUAAACUGAAGGAAGUAGUGGAAAAAGGAGUGGUAAUUCCAACAUGGAAUAUUUCACCAAUUAAGAAGGCCAAUGAAAUUAAGCCUCCUCAGUUUGUGGAUAUCCACCUUGAAGAAGAUGAUUCCUCAGAUGAAGAAUACCAGCCGGAUGAUGAAGAAGAAGAUGAAACUGCUGAAGAGAGCUUAUUGGAAAGUGAUGUUGAAAGCACUGCUUCAUCUCCACGUGGGGCAAAGAAAUCCAGAUUGAGGCAGUCUUCUGAGAUGACUGAAACAGAUGAGGAGAGUGGCAUAUUAUCAGAGGCUGAGAAAGUCACCACACCAGCCAUCAGGCACAUCAGUGCUGAGGUAGUGCCCAUGGGGCCCCCGCCCCCUCCAAAGCCGAAACAGACCAGAGAUAGUACUUUCAUGGAGAAGUUACAUGCGGUAGAUGAGGAGCUGGCUUCCAGUCCAGUCUGCAUGGAUUCUUUCCAGCCCAUGGAUGACAGUCUCAUUGCAUUUCGAACGCGUUCUAAGAUGCCCCUGAAAGAUGUUCCCCUGGGCCAAUUAGAGGCAGAGCUCCAAGCUCCAGACAUCACUCCAGAUAUGUAUGACCCCAAUACGGCAGAUGAUGAGGACUGGAAGAUGUGGCUGGGGGGACUUAUGAAUGAUGAUGUGGGGAAUGAAGAUGAAGCAGAUGAUGAUGAUGAUCCAGAAUAUAAUUUCCUGGAAGACCUCGAUGAACCAGACACAGAGGAUUUCCGGACUGACCGGGCAGUGAGAAUCACCAAAAAGGAAGUAAAUGAGCUGAUGGAAGAGCUGUUUGAAACUUUCCAAGAUGAGAUGGGAUUCUCCAACAUGGAAGAUGAUGGCCCAGAAGAGGAGGAGUGUGUAGCUGAGCCUCGUCCUAACUUUAACACCCCUCAAGCUCUACGGUUUGAGGAACCACUGGCCAACCUGUUAAAUGAACAACAUCGGACAGUGAAGGAGCUAUUUGAACAGCUGAAGAUGAAGAAAUCUUCAGCCAAACAGCUGCAGGAAGUAGAGAAGGUUAAACCCCAGAGUGAGAAAGUUCAUCAGACUCUGAUUCUGGACCCAGCACAGAGGAAGAGACUCCAGCAGCAGAUGCAGCAGCACGUUCAGCUCUUGACCCAAAUCCACCUUCUUGCCACCUGCAACCCCAACCUCAAUCCGGAGGCCACUACCACCAGGAUAUUUCUUAAAGAGCUGGGAACCUUUGCUCAAAGCUCCAUCGCCCUUCACCAUCAGUACAACCCCAAGUUUCAGACCCUGUUCCAACCCUGUAACUUGAUGGGAGCUAUGCAGCUGAUUGAAGACUUCAGCACACAUGUCAGCAUUGACUGCAGCCCUCAUAAAACUGUCAAGAAGACUGCGAAUGAAUUUCCCUGUUUGCCAAAGCAAGUGGCUUGGAUUCUGGCCACAAGCAAGGUUUUCAUGUAUCCAGAGUUACUUCCAGUGUGUUCCCUGAAGGCAAAGAAUCCCCAGGAUAAGAUCGUCUUCACCAAGGCUGAGGACAAUUUGUUAGCUUUAGGACUGAAGCAUUUUGAAGGAACUGAGUUUCCUAAUCCUCUAAUCAGCAAGUACCUUCUAACCUGCAAAACUGCCCACCAACUGACAGUGAGAAUCAAGAACCUCAACAUGAACAGAGCUCCUGACAACAUCAUUAAAUUUUAUAAGAAGACCAAACAGCUGCCAGUCCUAGGAAAAUGCUGUGAAGAGAUCCAGCCACAUCAGUGGAAGCCACCUAUAGAGAGAGAAGAACACCGGCUCCCAUUCUGGUUAAAGGCCAGUCUGCCAUCCAUCCAGGAAGAACUGCGGCACAUGGCUGAUGGUGCUAGAGAGGUAGGAAAUAUGACUGGAACCACUGAGAUCAACUCAGAUCGAAGCCUAGAAAAAGACAAUUUGGAGUUGGGGAGUGAAUCUCGGUACCCACUGCUAUUGCCUAAGGGUGUAGUCCUGAAACUGAAGCCAGUUGCCACCCGUUUCCCCAGGAAGGCUUGGAGACAGAAGCGUUCAUCAGUCCUGAAGCCCCUCCUUAUCCAACCCAGCCCCUCUCUCCAGCCCAGCUUCAACCCUGGGAAAACACCAGCCCGAUCAACUCAUUCAGAAGCCCCUCCGAGCAAAAUGGUGCUCCGGAUUCCUCACCCAAUACAGCCAGCCACUGUUUUACAGACAGUUCCAGGUGUCCCUCCACUGGGGGUCAGUGGAGGUGAGAGUUUUGAGUCUCCUGCAGCACUGCCUGCUGUGCCCCCUGAGGCCAGGACAAGCUUCCCUCUGUCUGAGUCCCAGACUUUGCUCUCUUCUGCCCCUGUGCCCAAGGUAAUGCUGCCCUCCCUUGCCCCUUCUAAGUUUCGAAAGCCAUAUGUGAGACGGAGACCCUCAAAGAGAAGAGGAGUCAAGGCCUCUCCCUGUAUGAAACCUGCCCCUGUUAUCCACCACCCUGCAUCUGUUAUCUUCACUGUUCCUGCUACCACUGUGAAGAUUGUGAGCCUUGGCGGUGGCUGUAACAUGAUCCAGCCUGUCAAUGCGGCUGUGGCCCAGAGUCCCCAGACUAUUCCCAUCACUACCCUCUUGGUUAACCCUACUUCCUUCCCCUGUCCAUUGAACCAGUCCCUUGUGGCCUCCUCUGUCUCACCCUUAAUUGUUUCUGGCAAUUCUGUGAAUCUUCCUAUACCAUCCACCCCUGAAGAUAAGGCCCACGUGAAUGUGGACAUUGCUUGUGCUGUGGCUGAUGGGGAAAAUGCCUUUCAGGGCCUAGAACCCAAAUUAGAGCCCCAGGAACUAUCUCCUCUCUCUGCUACUGUUUUCCCGAAAGUGGAACAUAGCCCAGGGCCUCCACUAGCAGAUGCAGAGUGCCAAGAAGGAUUGUCAGAGAAUAGUGCCUGUCGCUGGACCGUUGUGAAAACAGAGGAGGGGAGGCAAGCUCUGGAGCCGCUCCCUCAGGGCAUCCAGGAGUCUCUAAACAACCCUACCCCUGGGGAUUUAGAGGAAAUUGUCAAGAUGGAACCUGAAGAAGCUAGAGAGGAAAUCAGUGGAUCCCCUGAGCGUGAUAUUUGUGAUGACAUCAAAGUGGAACAUGCUGUGGAAUUGGACACUGGUGCCCCAAGCGAGGAGUUGAGCAGUGCUGGAGAAGUAACGAAACAGACAGUCUUACAGAAGGAAGAGGAGAGGAGUCAGCCAACUAAAACCCCUUCAUCUUCUCAAGAGCCCCCUGAUGAAGGAACCUCAGGGACAGAUGUGAACAAAGGAUCAUCAAAGAAUGCUUUGUCCUCAAUGGAUCCUGAAGUGAGGCUUAGUAGCCCCCCAGGGAAGCCAGAAGAUUCAUCCAGUGUUGAUGGUCAGUCAGUGGGGACUCCAGUUGGGCCAGAAACUGGAGGAGAGAAGAAUGGGCCAGAAGAAGAGGAAGAAGAGGACUUUGAUGACCUCACCCAAGAUGAGGAAGAUGAAAUGUCAUCAGCUUCUGAGGAAUCUGUGCUUUCUGUCCCAGAACUCCAGGAAACAAUGGAGAAACUGACUUGGCUGGCAUCUGAAAGGCGCAUGAGUCAGGAGGGUGAGUCUGAAGAAGAGAAUUCUCAGGAGGAGAACUCUGAGCCAGAAGAAGAGGAGGAAGAAGAAGCAGAAGGAAUGGAAAGCCUGCAGAAAGAGGAUGAAAUGACGGAUGAAGCAGUUGGAGACUCUGCUGAGAAGCCUCCUACUUUUGCUUCACCUGAGACUGCUCCAGAAGUGGAGACCAGCAGAACUCCACCAGGAGAGAGCAUCAAAGCUGCUGGAAAAGGCCGGAACAAUCAUCGAGCUCGCAACAAGCGGGGAAGUCGGGCUCGGGCCAGCAAGGACACCUCCAAGCUGCUGUUGCUGUAUGAUGAGGACAUUCUCGAGCGAGAUCCACUCAGGGAGCAGAAGGACUUGGCCUUUGCCCAAGCUUAUCUGACCAGGGUGCGAGAAGCCCUACAACAUAUCCCUGGCAAGUAUGAAGACUUCCUUCAAGUCAUCUAUGAAUUUGAGUCAAGUACCCAGAGACGGACGGCUGUAGAUCUCUACAAAAGCCUGCAAAUUCUGCUCCAAGACUGGCCUCAGCUGUUGAAAGACUUUGCUGCUUUCCUGUUACCUGAGCAAGCUCUGGCCUGUGGAUUAUUUGAGGAGCAGCAGGCUUUUGAGAAGAGCCGCAAGUUCCUUCGGCAGCUGGAGAUUUGCUUUGCAGAGAACCCCUCACACCACCAGAAGAUUAUCAAGGUCCUCCAAGGCUGUGCAGACUGCCUUCCCCAGGAGAUCACCGAGCUCAAGACACAGAUGUGGCAGCUCCUCAAGGGCCACGACCACCUGCAGGAUGAGUUUUCUAUCUUCUUUGACCACUUGCGCCCAGCAGCUAGCCGGAUGGGUGACUUUGAAGAGAUCAAUUGGACUGAGGAAAAGGAGUAUGAGUUUGAUGGCUUUGAAGAAGUGGCCCUGCCUGAUGUGGAAGAAGAGGAGGAGCCUCCCAAGAUACCCACAGCCUCAAAGAACAAGAGGAAAAAAGAGAUCGGGGUCCAAAAUCAUGAUAAGGAGACUGAAUGGCCAGAUGGGGCCAAGGACUGUGCCUGCUCCUGCCAUGAAGGAGGUCCAGAUUCCAAGCUGAAGAAGAGCAAAAGGCGGAGCUGUAGCCACUGUAGCAGCAAGGUCUGUGACAGCAAAUCCUACAAGAGCAAGGAGCCCCAUGAGUUGGUGGGCAGCAGCCCCCACCGAGAGGCUAGUCCUAUGCCUGGUGCUAAGGAAGCUGGGCAGGGCAAGGAUAUGAUGGAAGAGGAAGCCCCAGAGGAGCGGGAGAGCACUGAGGCCACCCAGAGCAGGACUGUCAGGACCACCAGAAAGGGAGAGAUGCCUGUUUCAGGAUUGGCAGUGGGGAGCACUUUGCCAUCCCCUCGAGAAGUGACUGUUACAGAACGGCUCCUCCUGGAUGGCCCACCACCUCAUUCACCAGAGACUCCUCAAUUUCCCCCCACAACUGGAGCUGUACUGUACACUGUUAAGAGAAACCAGGUUGGGCCUGAGGUUCGCUCCUGCCCCAAGGCAUCCCCCAGACUUCAGAAAGAGAGGGAGGGCCAAAAGGCAGUGAGUGAGUCAGAGGCUUUGAUGCUGGUCUGGGAUGCAUCAGAAACUGAGAAAUUGCCUGGUACCGUGGAACCCCCUGCUUCCUUCCUGAGUCCUGUUUCCUCAAAGACCAGAGAUGCAGGGAGAAGACAUGUGUCCGGGAAACCAGACACUCAAGAGAGAUGGCUGCCCUCAAGCAGAGCUCGGGUGAAGACAAGAGACAGGACGUGCCCUGUCCAUGAAUCUCCAUCAGGAAUUGACACCUCAGAGACUUCUCCCAAAGCCCCUAGAGGGGGUUUGGCUAAAGACAGUGGAACACAGGCCAAGGGUCCAGAGGGGGAGCAGCAGCCAAAGGCCGCAGAAGCUACGGUGUGUGCCAACAACAGCAAGGUCAGCUCCACUGGGGAAAAGGUUGUCCUGUGGACAAGGGAAGCUGACCGUGUGAUCCUCACCAUGUGCCAGGAGCAAGGGGCACAGCCACAGACCUUCAACAUCAUCUCCCAGCAGCUGGGAAAUAAGACCCCUGCUGAGGUUUCCCACCGUUUUCGAGAACUCAUGCAGCUCUUCCACACUGCCUGUGAAGCCAGCUCUGAGGAUGAGGAUGAUGCAACCAGUACCAGCAAUGCAGACCAGCUGUCUGACCAUGGGGACCUUCUGUCUGAAGAGGAGCUGGAUGAAUGAGACUCUGGGAAUCAUCUACACAGGACCAAACCCAACAGGCGCCCUGGCACCGGGGAGGGGGUAGUUGUACUCUGCUUGUACAGUCCUUGAGCCCAGUUUACAGAUCUGGAGAGCAGGAGGCCAGGACAAGGACAAAGGCUGGAGGAUGGAGUAGGACCCAGGGGCUCUGCCAUCCUAGGCAUCAUUCAAGGUCUUUUAUGAAGACUUUACAGAUGUCCUCUGUAAAUAGCAUCGAGAGUGGAGUUCAGCUCCUUUCUCUACUUUUUUUUGGUCUGAUGGCACAUAUUUAUUGUUCUGUGGUCUAAUCACAGUGUUUCUAAAUGUAAAAAGUGCAUAUGUUGGUGUAGCUAGUCCCGCGACAUUGAGCUCCUCUGCAUGAAGACACUGGGCUCCUGCAUCCAGCUGUUUUUAUUGCAAACUAGCUCCUUUCUCCCACACUGGGAACUUUAGUCCACGAGGCUGUCACCACCCUGGUAGCACUGGGCCAGGCUUUGUAGCUCCUGCAGCAGCUCUGCUACGUCAUCGUGCUCCACUCCAGCAUCCAUGAAGCUGGCCCAGCGCCGCAAGUCGAGUUUGGUGAGGUCUCUGGCCAAGGCUUCCAGGGUCUGGUGCAGGGACGAAGAGGAACACAGUGCCCCAAACACUGGGAUGCUCUCCACUGCUGUGGAGGGAGAGGAAACAGAGACCUGUAGAUGGAUGAUUAUUCUGCCCUGGGACUCGCCAAACUGAUAAGGAAGUCCAACCUUAGUAGACUUGAUUGUAAACUCAACAAAUUUGGUGUAUUGUCCCCUUAGUACACCAGUACUCCAGAGGAAGAAUGCUUUUCUUGGGAGCCAUAGGGUGAAUAAAGGAAUGUUUAACUGUGGACUUUUUCAGCACUUUUAAUCCAGGAAUGGAGAUAGUAAAACCUCUCCCAUACUUGAAAUCUCAGUUUUCUUCACCUCCUACAUACCUGCUCCCUUGGGGGAACCAUCCAGAACCAUACCCGGUGGACUGCAGCUUGAGAAGAGGUGGGGGUAAGGAGGAGCCACCCUGCAGGGAGUCAGCAGCAGAUGGGAAGAACUGUGGGGGCAGAGAACAGCCAUUAAGUGCGUAAGAAGUCAAGGGAGGGUUGCGGUUGGCAAGAAGGGCAGGAGCAACCGUUACACUGACCUCAUGACUCCAGGCUGCUGCUGUUGUAAAUACUGAGCCAAGAUUUCUUCCCCAGUGGUACAUGCAUGAAGGGCAGAGGGUGGAGGUGUCCCUGGGGUGAGCUGGCUGCCAUAACAAAGCCAAAACCACCAUUAGUCUGUGGCAGCAUGAAUAACAAACUAAGAAUUCUUUUUCUUUUUGAGACAGAGUUUUGCUCUUGUUGCCCAGACUGGAGUGCAAUGGUGUGAUCUCGGCUCACUGCAACCUCCACCUCCCAGGUUCAAACAAUUCUUCUGCCUCAUCCUCCCAAGUAGCUGGGAUUGCAGGCAUGUGCCACCAUGCCUGGCUAAUUUUAUGUUUUUAGUAGAGAUGGGGUUCACCAUGUUGGUCAGGCUGGUCUCGAAUUCCUGGCCUCAGGUGAUCUGCCCACCUCAGCCUCCCAAAGUGCUGGGAUUACAGGCGUCAGCCACCAUGCCUAGCCCAAGAAACUUAAGAAUUUUUAUGUUAUCAGGCCAUCAGCUGGAUCAAGAUAUUCAAAGCCCUUCUUUUUAUCCUUUUUAAGGGGUGGGGAGGGAACAACAUCAUUAGAAUGCCCGAGAAAUUAGGGGGAAAAGGACAUGAAACAAAAAUCUGACAAGGACUCCUAAGGACCAACAGCUCUCACCUUGUGUGGCAUGCUCUGUCUAUACCCUCAGCACCACUGACUGGGCAAAGCAACGUGUUCCAGAAGGCUCCCCACAUGCAGACAGUGGGGUCCAUGGGGUGGCUCCUCCAAACUGCAUCAGGGAAUCAGGAAGGGACUGGCCUGGAGCCAAGGGGAAAGGGAUGAUUGCUCCUGCUGUCACCACUUAAAGAGAAGGAAGAGAACACGUUAUAGGACAUUUUCUCAGCACUGACCCAACCCCUCACAAAGCUUCAUACCUUUUUCCCACAGAAGCUCAGCAUGUCAGCCAGAUGAACCAUGGAAACUGGAGAGGAACACAGGCGAUAAGGAACAGUGACUGUGUCCAGGGCUGUAGCCAGGAUGGCACUGCAGUGGAAGGGCAGAAUGGCCUGUAAGAAGACACCAAGAGGGGCACUUGGCCUCGGGCCUGGAAAAGAAUGUGUGGAGGCAGAAUGUUAACACCAGAGAGACCCAGGGGAUGAAUCAGGGGUAUGUUUGACCCCAGGCUGGACAAGCAUAGGACAGUGUGAUCUGAGAGGCCACAUCACAGCUGAGUUCAAGCUCGGGCCUCAGGAACAGAGCCAGUACAGACAGCGACUGACUGGGAGCAUGAGGAGGCCCUGUAGCCUGCCGCAGUCAGAACAAGAGCACCGAGACUUACAUCAUAAUGCAGGUAAGGGAAGUUGACAGGUGGCUCAGGUCGCAGGCCCAGGCUCCCACCCAAGGACAAGGGGCAGACGAGAGCUGUGAGCAGUCAGGUGCACGAGACCAAAAGCUGUGUUUAAUAGACGAUAGAUGUUUCUCUGGGCCUCCUCGUAAAGAAAAAAACCAGUUUGCAUUAAGCCACUCUCCCAAUGGGAUUCGAAUGUUUACUCCUCCAAGUUCCACUCACCCCACGAUGGUAGGGACCAGGUAGCAGGCCCCAAGUUAUUAUUCCCCGCCCUGAAUAUUCAUCUUGUAGCAGCUCUGCCGCCUUCGCGCCUACCCCAGAGAAGCCAUCGUGCAGGUCACACAGGAUCUGGAAGCCCUGGGCGGGGGUGAGUGACGAAAGAUAGUUAGCAGGAUGAGAAGAGCUUCCACCCUGGAGUGCACAUUGCCACGCCACUACCUGCAAGUAGUCACAUUCCUCCACGUAGAAAUGCAGCCUGUCCUCCAGCUCUUCCUGGUACUUGGGUUCCUUUAGGACACUUUCCCCUUGGCCAAAAGCCUCCAGCCGACCUGCUUCCCUGCCACAAGUAAACACGAUCCAAGACUUACAUCUCUUCCCUCAACUCCUCAGCCUCUUGUCCUGGGGAAGGGCAGGGAAGAUGGCCUCAAGAGCCUCAUCCUGCAUUGGUGGGGACCCAUGUUUCUUGCCUCAAAGCCUCUGGGGUCCCCAUACCCAUCGUGGUUGUACUUCUGAAUCAUACAGAUGCUCCGGGGAUGGAGAUGGACUCUGAGGAAGUCUGACCAGACCCUGAUGCUGGCCUCUGUAGGGAUAAGUGGUUUUGGAGUUGUAGCGGUGGGGAGUGGUGAGGAACCUGAAGACAAGCAGAGGAAAUGUACCUUUCUCCAUGUUUCUGCUCUACCCAAGCCCCCAUCCAUCAGUAUCUGGAGAAGUCUCACCUUUGCCAUUGGGAAUGGAUUUGACCCUCCAGACACCAUCACUACUCAGCACUCCCUGGGAGGGGUCAGAAAAAUCGACAUUUAGUUCCAGGCAGUUUAGAGGCAAAGGUUGCUUCAUCCUCCUUGAGUUGGCUGGCCACACCGCAUAGCCUCCUUUCUGUUCACCGAGUCGCAGUCCUUAGGAAAAGGAGUGCUUUUUCCCAAAAUAUCAUUCUAAGACAUUUAAAAUGAUUAAAAUCCCCGUUUACCUGCCCCUAUGGAGACCCUCAGGUUGUGGCACCGGGUUAAAAAGUUCAGGACAGAGGCCCUCACCUCUGCACUCAGAAAGUCUUGGAGAUAAGGGUUCUUGGGAUAGAGUUCCUCUUUGUGUGUGGUGAGCUUCCCCUGCCUGAAAGAGUUUGGAGAUUGAUCAAAGAAACUGCACUCUGAUCAGAGUUAUCCAGCGUUCUGCGUACAUACACGAUCCCCACCCUUAUCCAUACAUCAGUUACACACCAUGCUAUUGCAGCAUCCAACUGUUUGUCCCUGUAGAGUCCACCUUCCUCUUUUAGGGAGCUCAAACUACCUGUACAGAAAUAACAGAGACAAUGUUAGGUCAAAGCCUGGGCACCCUUCCCCUCUAGCUAACCUUCCUCUGAUCACCUGACAACCUGCUGUCACCAUCUCUCCAGCACUUGGCUCUUCCAAGCUUUCUGGGAUAUACACUAGUUGGGGGAAAAACCUUGGCUUAGGAGAAUCUAGAUUCCAUCUUUCGGUUCCCAGCUUAGUCAUUAGCUGUGGGACGCGGGGGGAACCACAUCCAGGGGUCUGACAGGAGUGCUGCAGUUCAAGUCCUCACUGUCUCCAGGGCCUAGCAGCCUAUUCCCGAAAUGGCUCUUGAGCAACUGUCGUGGGCCCCUCGAGUGUUGGCAUGUUGUGCUCAGCUCCUCAUCUCCGGUCCUGGAGCUCGGUAAAGUGGGAGGGUCUUGAAGAUAACGGCAGCGCAAGGACUAGGCACGCGGAAGGGAAAUAAGGGGCAUCGGCUAACUCUGCCACCACCUCACCCUUCAGAUCCAUGAGGAUGAGUCGCGGCGUGUAGGUCUCCUGGCCGUGCAGCGUCCGGCCCGUACGAUACAGGACGUCGGGGCACAGCUCUCCCGGGGGCUCCUUGGAAUCGGUCGCUCGGCCCAGCGCAGCAUCCUGGGGAAGCAGAGAGGACGAGGCAGGCCGGCUGAACGUCGGGACUGUAGAUCCCGAAGGGCUCCUCGGGGGCAGCUGCCGGCUGACCUCACCUGCUGGUUCCACCAGUGCGCGCCCACGAAACCGGCAAAAUGUCCCAACUGCAGUAUCUCUCCGCUGGCUGAUAGCUCCCCGGGCAAAAAUGAAACCUUGCCAGAAUAGCGGAAGCUCCGCUAAAGCCUCCCAUGCCCCCUCAUCUCUUCAGAAGUCACACGGAUCACGACUCUUCAGAAGUCCACAGAUCCCCGUGGACUGACCUAGCUAUCAUAUCUGUAUCAUUUACAUGUAUUAAUCUAUCUCUGUGUAUGUAACACUUUAUGUAAAUAGAGUAUUGGCGUCUGUCUUUUGCUCAAUAUGGUUUAUGCAAUUUAUGUUUUUGCAUAUAUAUUUUUCAUCUCUGUGGAAUAGUCCAUUGUAUGAAUACACCACCACUGAUCUAUUCUAAAGAAUGAAUAUAUUCUGCUGAUAAUA